ACUCUUCGUUUCAGCCCUGGCGCGGUCCUGUGGUGAACUCCUUGUCUCUAUGGCGACUGGACGCGGUCGGAUCUUGCAGCAGCACUGGCUCGGCCUCCAGACGCUGCGCGGGCCCAGCAGGGGCGGUGGCGCGGCCCGGGGGCGCGCCAGGGCCUUUGGGUGCAGGUGACUGUAGGGCCUGCGGGUGGGGUCCCCUGGCGGGAAGCCCGUCACUGCGCGGCCCCGCUCUCUUCACCGUGUAUUUUAUUCGUCCAGCUUGGCGCAAGGCCCGUGGCCGUCUUCAACGUGAGAAGGGUCUUGCUCAUCUGCUUUCCAGAAGCAUCUUCAGCGUGAAGAAGUAAAAUGAGCCAGUGCAUCAGAAGUAUCAGCAUGCAUAAUGGUACCUUAUGAAAUCCCUCUCAUUAUAUCGUGAGCUGUUCCCUAGCUGUGUACCCAUCACUGCAGUUAGUUUACAGAUGGAGGGAUAAUGCCAAGAAUGGUUUACAUUCUUGAGGAUUAUCUUUCUGCUUGUAAGACUCCUUGAUUUAUAAAUAGGGAAAGUCAUGCAUAUUUUGCCUUCUAAUAAACCAAUGGUCUAUGUUUAAGCACACAAAGGGAGUCUAUUACAUACUAGUUGAACUACUUGUUUUUUCCCCCUGAAUCUCCAGAACUAUGUCCUGUGUCCUCUCUAGGUCUCCAUUACUUCCACUUACCUGUUUUCAGAAGCCCAGCCCUGUUGCUUAGUGCUGUGAUAAUAGUUCUUAAUUGAAUACCUAUAAUGCUAGACAUACCACAAGCCUUGUCACAAAUAGAAUGGUGACAAUGCCUGCAAAAAUUCUUUUAUGUAGGAGAAAAAGCAGGAAUUUAAAUAGGAAACUUGAACUUUUAAUCAAUUUGCUGCUAUUACUAAAAUUAGUCUUUACAUAGUGCUCUAUUAGGGGGAAGCAGAAUGAUUUUUAUAUGAUGAAUCUUUUAUCCUUUGUAAGUUGAGUGAACUUCCUGGAUUGAUAUAAUUAGAGGGCCUGUCAUUAUGCCUGGCAUGGGAACCUGCAUUUCAAGCUGAUUUGGAAAUGUAUGCAUUAUUUUUGGUAAAGAAAAGUCCGCUGCUAAAAAUAGAAUGAUUGACUAUGGUCAAAGCAGGUGGUUAUUUUAAUAUAUCGCUGUGGAAAAUUAGAUGUUGUUAAGGAAUCAGUGUUCCCUUUUAACACAAAAUGUGAAUAUGUAUAAAUAUCACAAACUGUAAGAAGUGUAGCAGAAAGCGUAUUAAGUUGGCUUAAUUUGUACCUGCUGUAAUUUAUUUGAUUUGCCAGAUAUUUAAAAUGAAGCACAGUCAUUAGGUUUUUAAAAUAUUGGACUUAUUGAAAGCUAUCAGACAAAAACCUGUCACUUGAAAAAAAGUGUUUUCAAACUAAAUUUAUCUUGCUAAAUGUAUCAGUGUAUGUCUACACUUAACCUUGUAGACGUAUAGAUUCGCAUAAAAACAUAAAUAGAACUUGCUGAUUUGUUAAUUAUGUGGACCUUAAAAAUGUGCAAUUGGGGCCGGGUGCAGUGGCUCACGCCUGUGAUCCCAGCACUUUGGGAGGCGGAGGCGGGCAGAUCUGGAGGUGAGGAGAUCGAGACCAUCCUGGCUAACACUGUGAAACCCCGUCUCUACUAAAAAUACAAAAAAAUUAGCCCGGCAUGGUGGCGGGCGCCUGUAGGCUCAGGUACUCAGGAGGCUGAGGCAGGAGAAUGGCGUGAACCCAGGAGGCGGAGCUUGCAGUGAGCCGAGAUAGCGCCACUGCACUCCAGCCUGGGCGACAGAGCCAGACUCUGUCGCAAAAAAAAAAAAAAAAAAAAAGUGCAGUUGGUUUAUUUUAUGGAUAAAUAGAAAUGUGUUUCCAAUAGUGUUAAAAGGUACACUGAUAAGAUGUAUGGUCUCAUGUAAGACAUGGUACAGAGAGCUCUGACAGGACAUUAAGGAGAUGGGCGUCUCAGAGACUGUCUUUGCUUCUAGCUUGGGACCUUAAGUUUCUUUAGUUGCCUUGUUAGAGCCUUAGCCUUGUAAACUGAAAUGAGGGACUCUAUGAGAUCCAUUUUAAUUGUGAAAAAACAAAACAGCAAGAAAUAAGCUUUGACGUUUUAAAAGUGUGAAAACAUGUUUGUAAUAAAAUAGCCUUCAUAUUCCAAUUAAAUAAAGGAUGAAAUGUCUUAAAGCACUUACACAUUACCUUGUGCAGAGUAUAUGAUUAAGAAGUAUUUGUAGAAUUGAACUAACUAAGCCCUGUUAAAUGUUUUAGCCAAAGAUAGAGGCAUAUCCAUUCGUUACUGAAUUAGGGUUUCAGAUUAGGGAAAAGCAUUUGGUACUUAAAAAAAAUAACUAGUACCAAACAGGAUUUAUUUGCUUAAUCGUUAUUUAAAACUAUCUUUGAGUGGGGAGAGUUACAGCAUGACUUUGAGGAACUUACUAAGAUCAUUUUAUUUACAUAUAUUUUAUAUGCAUAUAUGUUUACAAAACAGGUGACUUUAUUUCACUGGUGUUUUCACAGUAAUCUUUCAUAAAUUCGGGACACACAAGUUAAGGUUUUCAGUAAGAACUUGGUGGUGGAUUAAGCCAGUAUGUAUUCUUGAAACAUCUAAGCACCCUGGCGCUGUGCUUCUCAAACGAGUAGUUGUAGUGGGUGGGGAACACAUAGAGCAUCUUCUUUGUCUGCAAAAUCAACACAAAGGCUUUGGGGAAAAUGUUAAAUAAUUUAACUGGUAAAUAAUAUAAUACAUUUUUAUGAUAGGACAAAGACAGAUUAUUUAGUAGAAUGCAGUAUUUGCUUUAAUUUUUAAGAUCAAUUGGGAGACUCCUAAGAAAUUUUGAGUUUGCUGCAGACUGUACCCCCAGAUUUCGGGGGACCUGGUUUCAGUUUCUUUGCAAGAGUUCUGUUGCUAGGAAUGCCUUUGAGAACCACUGCUCCAGUCUCAAGGAUUGUGCUGUCAAACUGUGAUUCCCUGGCCUUCUUUUGCAUGUGACUCUUAGGUUUGAAAUUAAAACAACACCCCCACCCCCCAACUUAUUACAGAUUCAAUAUGCUAAGAAAAAUUAGAACAUACAUGGAGUUAUGCCCCCUAAAUCGUCCCCAUUUAAAAAGACCUUCACCAACAGAUUUUGUAAUCCUAUGAAUCAGAUCUGUUAACUGUUAAACCUUGGUGUCUCUAGAUCUCUUUUCUUUGUAUGCAUAUAUUUACUUUUCCUCUUAGAGAAAUAGAAAAAUAAGUUUAUGUAUUAGGUUGGUGCAAAAGUAAUUGUGGUUUUUGUUACUGAAAGUAAUGGCAAAAGCCGCAAUUACUUUAGCACCAACCUAGUAGUAUAUACUGAUAUAACCUGCUUUCUCAGUUAUACUGUUAGUGAUUCAGCGAUAUUUAUUGAAUGCUGCUCGCAUGCCAGGCAUAUUGUGGGUGCUGAACGAUCAGCAGUGAACAAACCCAUGCAGUAUAACUGCCCAUGUCAUUCCAGCGAUAGUAAGCAAGACAGGCAGGUUAAAUGUAUAGUGUUGGAUGGUGAUGUGUGCUAAGGAGAGAAACAGAGAAAGGACACAAAGUGCAUGUGUGUGUGGCAGAGGGGACUGGAUUGCAGUUUAAAUAUAACAGCCAAGGAAGGUCUCAGUGAGAUGGUGACAUUGUAGUAAAUGGCUGAAGAAAGUGAGGGAGCAAGCCAUAUAGACACCUGGAGGCCAUCAGGGACCUGUUUCUAAUUCAAACACUUAACCUGGGUUGAAAAAUCUAUAUUUUAAUUGACUAGACAUUGUUAACUCUAUGGAGACCAUGCAAUUUAACCAAUCUCUAUACCGUUUUUAGUAUUUUUUUCCCCCAGUGCAGACAACUCUGAGAUGGACAUUCUUGAGUGAACUAUCUGUGCACAUUUCUAGAAGUGGAAUUCCUGGCUUAAAAGAGCAUAUGUGCUUUUUAAGGAUCCUGGAUUCCAAUAUCAGAUUUGGCUUUCCAUAACGUUUGUACCACUGUAUCUUGUCUUACGGGCAGUAAAUGAGGAUGCCUGUUUCUUUGUAACAUAGCCAGCAUGAAUCAUCAUCAUUUAUUUGGUAUUUGCCAAUUGCUAGAUUAAAAUUGAUCCAUCAGAUGAAUUUACUUUUCUUUGGUUCUCUUGGAAAGGCCUAAGGUAACAGUUUUUAUUUUUCUGGCUUCUUAUUGAGGAAAUAAACAAUGACAAAAAGCUGUUACUGAUUCAGUAAGGUAUUUAUUUAAUAUCUUAAAUAAAAUUAUAUUUGAUGAACUACAAUAAUAUUUAUGUUUAAAGUAUAUAUAGAAUUAUUCAUAUGAUGCUUAGGGUAUGUGUGGACUCCGAUUCUAGGUACAGCCAACCCCCACACUCCCAUAGGCUUAAGGGUUACAGGUUUGGAGCUCCUGAUAGGAAUUGUUAUUGUUUGAUGAAGGAAUGAUAGAAAUUCCCUUUAUUUGAAGCUUAAGUGUUAGAAUCCUUUAUCAAUUGUAGAUAUUUUAUCUUUGAAUAUGUAAUAUAAGUCAAUACAGACUUUACAACAAUAAUAACCAUUUAAAAAUAAGUCAUGCUUUUAAAUAAUUUUAGAAUGUAUUACAAAUUUGUUUACUGUGUUGACUAUUGACAGUAAACAAAGUGUAUUAUACCUUCUAAAGUUAUUUAUGUCCUUCUGGAACACCAGGAUGUGACUUUCUUUAGAUAUAGGGUCUCUGCAGGUAUAAUUAGUUAAGAUGAGGUCAUACUGGAUGAGGGAGGGUCCUAAGUGCAAUAUGAAUGAUAUCCUUAUAAGAAGAGGCACAGAGACAGAUAUGCCUAGAGGGAAGAUUGCUCUGUGAAGAUGGGGGCAGAGAUUAGAGUUAUGCUGACACAAACUAAGGGACACCAAGGAUUUCUGGCAACCACCAGAAAAAGGAAUGAUCCUCUCUAGAGCCUUCAGAGGGAGCACGGCCCUGUUGACAACUUGGGUUUUGGACAUCUGGCUACUGAGACAUAAUACAUUUCUGUUGUUCUGAGUCACCCAGUUUGUGAAGGUAGUCUUAGGAGACGAAUGCAAUUAGGAAAUGAUAUUUUACUUAUGAUUACUAUGUUAGGACCAUGUUAAUGGAGCCUAAGCUUUUCUCCUGUGGAAAUCUGUGUUUAAACAAAAUUUCUAACAGAAGUACAAAAAUAUAUAACAGGUAGAAUUAUCUGAUUAAAGGAGGAGAGGGUAUUGCAAAAAUGUCCCAAUUAGCAUUUCUUCCUGUCCUUUCUCCCUGUCUUCCUGCCCUGCAGAGCACAGAUUGAAAACCAUUGGCUAGAAAGUCAUAUAAGACCAAAAGUAUAUUAAGCACCUUUUACUGAAGCUGGGAUGGAAAGGCAUGUGGAGCCAGCAUUUUUUUUUCCUCGGUGCAUUUUUACUCUUACAGGAUCUGGAAAAGUUUACCUUAUGCAACUUCUUUGUUGAGAUGCCAGUGGAGCAGCUGAUCACUAAUAUUUGUGGAGGGCCUACCCUGUACCAGCUACUGUGCUUUUUUCUAGAGAGAAAAAUUCACAAAGGGAAGAGGAAUUUACUCUGUAGCUGCUUGGAAGCAUGUGGAGACUUGUGCCUGGGAAGCAGGGCAGCCAGGUGCCAGUGGGUGAUUUGAGUGCGUGCUGCAUAUCAUGAUGCUGUCUUGCGGUAGGCUCCAGGCUACACUGUCACCUGGCCAGCUGAUGCCUAGGGCAAGGGCUCCUUUUUCACCACUUGUGUCAUCUAAUAGGUUGUGCUCAGAGUUGAGGGCCAUCCUCUGUUAAGACCAGUUGUGUGUGGAUUUCAUACUUCAGCUUUCAGGGGGGUUGGUUCAUUACUUUUUCUUCCAAGUUCUUAAGGCAUCUCUUUUUUUGCUCCCAAUUGUUGCCCUCCUUUAUGAAUGUUGUUUCAACUAUAUCUGGGGAAUUGGCCUGGUGUGAAAAACUGAGGGUGGUUAAACUGUCAGUGCACAAAGUACACAUUCAAAGCAAUGAUGUUGGUGAACUGAGCGUAUACAUAAUGUACUCUCUAGGAUUUAGCCACUUCUUAAAUAGCACAUCAGGAAGGAGGUGCGCCAAUAUCCAAUACCUGUGUGUUGUAUGUUGCUUAAAGCAGAAGCUUCCAAACCUUUCCUAGAGAAAUAGUGUAACCAUUCAUGGCUCUCCGGGUGUGCUGCUGCCUAGACAUGGAGGCUGUGAGCUGUAUGAUUUUCUGGUGUUUCAGAUUCCCUCAAGGUGCUGCUGAGUACUACUGGUUUUGAGGACUGAUCUUAAUAAAAUUUACUUUAGGAACCUCUGAAAAAGACUCACUGCAUAAAAAUAUUAUAUGCUAUUUCAUUGAAUCUAAAAAACCAUUCAUUCUAAGAUGCACUACUGUUUUCUGUACCACUAAAAUAAAAAGAUGGCCAGUGAAAAUAUAUUGCAUUGAAUGGGAGAGGUUAAAAUGUAAAAGUUUGUGGAUGAGUAUUUGGUAGUUUGUCUAUGACUGCAAAAGCUAGAGUUGGAACCCUCAAAGAUCAGAAAAGUUGUAGAUUGUGUUUUAUGUUGACAGUUCUAGUUUACUAAUAGUAAGUUUUUUAAAAAAAACUUUAAUGGUUUCUGUUUUAUCCAAAUUGGCUAAUCAGUACACUAACUGUAUCCUUUUUGUUUCCAUUAAAUGUAUUUGGUAACACCUCUUUGACAUGUUGAAAGCCUACAGUGAGAGUGUAUAUUUCUAAACCUUUGGGUGAAAGCACAUCAGAGUAAGUACGGUCUUGAGGUUUCCUUACCAGGACACUAAAGGUUUCACUGCCUCUUCCUCCCUUCUCCCUGCCUUUCUUCCUUCCUUACCAUCAAGGUCUCACUGUCUCUUCCUCCCUUCUCCCUGCCUUUCUUCCUUCCUUACCAUCAAGGUCUCACUGUCUCUUCCUCCCUUCUCCCUGCCUUUCUUCCUUGCUUACCAUCAAGGUUUCACUGUCUCUUCCUCCCUUCUCCCUGCCUUUCUUCCUUCCUUCCAUCUUUUCUUCUUCCCUUCCUUUUUUUCUUUGCAGAAAUUAAGUUUUUCAGUGAGUAAUCUUUGGAGUUUAUGAAUCCUUUGGAAUUUUGUAGAAGGGAAUAGAUAAUUCACCUCAUUUGGUAAUUACAUAAUUUGAAUUUCCCACAUUUACUUUCAGAAAGGGGCCAGGGGUCAAGCUUUCUGCAGGCUCUGCUGCCCUGAGGUGCCAUGCCGGAGGUGGACAGCACUGGGAGAGCUCUUUCUCCUGCUGUUCUGGGUUCCUGGAUGGAAUGCCUUCAGAAAUCUUGCUGAAGAUAUUUUCCUACUUGGAUGCUGUGAGCCUUCUGUGUACUGGAUGUGUGAGCAGGCGCUUUUAUCAUCUAGCCAAUGACAAUUUUAUUUGGAUCGGAAUCUACUCAACUGCUUUUUCACCUGCAAGAUCAAAUUGGAAAUUUAAUUCAGUAGAGAAGAUAGCUAUGUCUAUGAGCUUUCUGUCAGUUCAGGAUAAAGAAGCUGGUUAUUGGAAGAAAGAAUAUAUCACAAAACAAAUAGCAUCUGUAAAAGCCGCACUAGCUGACAUUCUCAAACCUGUCAACCCUUACACAGGCCUUCCAGUUAAGACCAAAGAGGCCCUCAGAAUAUUUGGUUUAGGUUGGGCAAUUAUACUGAAAGAAAAAGGUGGAAAAGAAUAUAUCAUGGAGCAUGUUGAUCUUUCCAUAAAUGACACAUCAGUUACUGUUAUAUGGUAUGGCAAAAAAUGGCCAUGCCUAGCAUCAUUGUCAACCUUAGAUUUAUGUGGCAUGACACCAGUUUUUACCGACUGGUAUAAAACUCCCACCAAACAUAGACUCCGAUGGCAUUCUUUAAUUGCAAAGUACAAUCUGAGUCAUUUGACCAUAUCUACCAUGAUUGGCUGUGACAGACUCAUUCGGAUCUUCUGCCUGCACCCUGGCCUCCUGGUGGGAGUGUGGAAGAAGGAGGAAGAACUGGCUUUUGUUAUGGCAAAUCUUCAUUUUCAUCACCUUGUGGAGAGGAGCACAUUAGGCUCGGCUACUAUCCCCUAUGAACUGCCUCCACAUAGCCCCUUUUUGGAUGAUAGCCCCGAGUAUGGACUGCACGGCUACCAACUCCAUGUUGAUCUGCACAGCGGUGGGGUUUUCUACCUAUGUGGUACAUUUCGCAAUCUCUUCACCAAGAGAGGAAAUAUUGAAAAUGGACAUGUGAAGCUCAUUGUUAUACAUUUAAAAAAUAACAGAGAACACCUACCUCUUAUUGGAAAAGUUGGCCUCUCGUGGAAAACUGAUAUUUUUGAUGGCUGUAUAAAGAGUUGUUCCAUGAUGGACGUAACUCUUUUGGAUGAACAUGGGAAACCCUUUUGGUGUUUCAGUUCCCCGGUGUGCCUGAGAUCGCCUGCCACACCCUCUGACAGCUCUAGCUUCUUGGGACAGACAUACAACGUGGACUACGUUGAUGCGGAAGGAAGAGUGCACGUGGAGCUGGUGUGGAUCAGAGAGACCGAAGAAUACCUUAUUGUCAACCUGGUCCUUUAUCUUAGUAUCGCAAAAAUCAACCAUUGGUUUGGGACUGAAUAUUAGCAGUAGGUGGCAAAUUAUUGUUGUUAUUUAGUUGUUUAUUUUUGACUGGCUUUGUUCUUGGUGUUGAAAAUUAAAAUAAAGCAAAUCUGCAGA